CCCUCCCUCUUUCCCUCCCGCGAGCCUCGGGGUUCCUCAGCUGGCUGAGGUGGAGUCAGUGUCAGUCAGGGAGGCGAACUGCUGAGCACUGGCCGCGGACGCUCCGUUGCAGUCUCGCCCAGGGGCCGGUACCUGCGCUCGCGCCGCCGGGUUGAAAGGAUGAAGCCGCAGCUGGAGCAGCCACCCUAUGAUUGGCUGUGGCGCUUGUGAACCCAAAGUAAAGAUGGCGGGCGGGCAGGCAGCCGCCGCACUGCCCACUUGGAAGAUGGCGGCGCGCCGCAGCCUCAGCGCUCGCGGCCGGGGGAUCCUGCAGGCGGCUGCGGGGCGGCUGCUGCCGCUGCUCCUGCUGAGCUGCUGCUGCGGUGCGGGCGGCUGCGCAGCGGUGGGCGAGAAUGAGGAGACGGUGAUCAUCGGGCUGCGACUGGAGGACACGAACGACGUGUCGUUCAUGGAAGGGGGGGCGCUGCGGGUGAGCGAACGGACCCGGGUCAAGCUGCGGGUGUACGGGCAGAACAUCAAUAACGAGACGUGGUCCCGCAUCGCCUUCACCGAGCACGAGCGGCGGCGCCACAGCCCGGGGGAGCGCGGGCUGGGGGGCCCCGCGCCGCCAGAGCCGGACAGCGGCCCCCAGCGAUGCGGCAUCCGCACCUCAGACAUCAUCAUCUUGCCCCACAUCAUUCUCAACCGCCGCACCUCGGGCAUCAUCGAGAUCGAGAUCAAACCGCUACGCAAGAUGGAGAAGAGCAAGUCCUAUUACCUGUGCACGUCGCUCUCCACGCCCGCCCUGGGCGCCGGCGGCUCGGGGUCCACGGGUGGCGCCGUCGGGGGCAAGGGUGGCUCGGGGGUGGCCGGGCUCCCGCCGCCCCCGUGGGCCGAGACCACCUGGAUUUACCACGACGGCGAGGACACCAAGAUGAUCGUAGGCGAAGAGAAGAAGUUCCUGCUGCCCUUCUGGCUGCAGGUGAUCUUCAUUUCGCUGCUGCUGUGCCUGUCGGGCAUGUUCAGCGGCCUCAACCUGGGGCUCAUGGCCCUGGACCCGAUGGAGCUGCGCAUCGUGCAGAACUGCGGCACGGAGAAGGAGAAGAAUUACGCCAAGCGCAUCGAGCCGGUGCGCAGGCAGGGCAACUACCUGCUGUGCUCACUGCUGCUGGGCAACGUGCUGGUCAACACCACGCUCACCAUCCUGCUCGACGACAUCGCCGGCUCGGGCCUCGUGGCCGUGGUAGUCUCCACCAUCGGUAUCGUCAUCUUCGGAGAGAUCGUGCCCCAGGCCAUCUGCUCCCGGCAUGGCCUGGCUGUGGGGGCCAACACCAUCUUCCUCACCAAGUUUUUCAUGAUGAUGACCUUCCCCGCUUCCUACCCGGUCAGCAAGCUGCUGGACUGCGUCCUGGGCCAGGAGAUAGGCACCGUCUAUAACCGGGAAAAACUGCUGGAGAUGCUCCGGGUCACCGAUCCCUACAACGACCUCGUUAAGGAGGAGCUGAACAUCAUCCAAGGGGCGCUGGAGCUCCGCACCAAGACGGUGGAGGACGUGAUGACCCCACUCCGGGACUGCUUCAUGAUCACCGGCGAAGCCAUCCUGGACUUCAACACCAUGUCUGAGAUCAUGGAGAGCGGCUACACCCGCAUUCCAGUGUUUGAAGGGGAGCGCUCCAAUAUCGUGGACCUGCUGUUUGUCAAAGACUUGGCCUUCGUGGAUCCCGAUGACUGUACCCCCCUGAAAACCAUCACCAAAUUUUAUAACCACCCCUUGCACUUUGUUUUCAAUGACACCAAGUUGGACGCUAUGCUGGAAGAAUUUAAGAAAGGUAAAUCUCACCUGGCUAUCGUGCAGCGGGUAAACAAUGAGGGAGAAGGGGAUCCAUUUUAUGAAGUUCUGGGAAUCGUCACCUUAGAAGAUGUGAUUGAAGAAAUCAUCAAAUCUGAGAUUCUUGAUGAAACAGAUUUAUACACUGACAACAGAACGAAAAAGAAAGUGGCUCACCGGGAACGAAAGCAAGAUUUUUCUGCCUUUAAGCAGACAGACAGUGAGAUGAAGGUUAAAAUAUCACCACAGCUCCUCCUGGCCAUGCACCGUUUCCUAGCAACAGAAGUAGAAGCAUUUAGCCCAUCCCAGAUGUCAGAGAAGAUCCUUCUAAGGCUGCUAAAGCACCCCAAUGUCAUCCAGGAACUGAAAUAUGAUGAGAAGAACAAGAAAGCCCCCGAAUACUACCUCUACCAGCGCAACAAGCCAGUAGACUACUUCGUUCUCAUUCUGCAGGGGAAAGUGGAAGUUGAAGCUGGGAAAGAAGGUAUGAAGUUUGAAGCGAGCGCCUUCUCAUACUAUGGCGUGAUGGCCCUGACAGCCUCUCCAGUUCCUUUGUCCCUGUCUCGUACCUUUGUUGUCAGCAGAACAGAGUUGUUAGCAGCAGGUUCUCCAGGUGAAAAUAAGUCCCCUCCUCGCCCAUGUGGCUUGAAUCACUCAGACUCUCUCAGUCGAAGCGACCGGAUUGACGCCGUCACACCAACACUGGGGAGCAGCAAUAACCAGCUCAAUUCUUCGCUCCUCCAAGUCUACAUCCCCGAUUACUCGGUGCGAGCCCUUUCGGAUCUGCAGUUUGUUAAGAUCUCAAGACAGCAAUACCAAAAUGCCUUGAUGGCAUCCCGGAUGGACAAAACCCCCCAGUCUUCAGACAGUGAAAACACUAAAAUCGAAUUGACUCUUACGGAGCUGCAUGACGGGUUGCCAGACGAGACAGCCAACCUGCUCAACGAACAGAACUGUGUGACGCACAGUAAGGCCAACCACAGCCUGCACAACGAAGGCGCCAUCUAGGCCGCGCUGGCUGCACCCGCCCAGGCCCGCACCCGCCCAGUCCCGAGGGCCCGGCCCUGUCUGCCCAUGACUUCACUGGUGUGAGCUUGUCCGCCAUGCUGUACCCUGCAACAUCCUGAGACCAAAGACCUUGUGCCCUUCCCAGGAGCCGCGGAGGAGGACAGUGAGGGAGGAAUGGAAACGAGAGAUGUGAAGUUGGCAGCCGGGGCAUGGCGUUCAAGAUUUUGGAGAUGAACUGAUUCCGCCCAAAUAGAAUCAUGUUUAUUUUUUCAGCUCUCCCUUUUAUCAUUAUUCACACUCCUCUGCCCUCGAUUUGCAUGAAGUUGAAAAUUGUUGCGAUUUAUUUUUUCAAGAGAUCAUGUUUUUAAAGUGUCUUUUGCAGAGUUUUAAGUUGUUCUGUCUGAACUCUGCUGUGAUCCCAUGAUGUGACCCUGAUGGGCUGGACUUGCCCCUCCGGUAGCCUUCCUUGGCCCUCCCAGCGAGGGGCACCCUUCCUCUGUGCCCCAGUGGGCAUCACCGUCGAUCUCGCUGGCUGAAUGAAGAAGACCGUGUUACUGCAGAACCUGCCAAGUCUGUCAUCACUGUGGGGUGUAGCCUGCCUCAGAGGGACCUGCAAUCACCUCUCUGAGCUCAGUGGUAUUUUGAGAAUUUAAUGUUUAACUGUACCCCUUUCCCUCAGGAAGAUUUAACAUUUGCUUGGGAAUGUGAUUUUGCUCCCACCCUAAGGAAUUUUUAUCACCAAAAUGAAUGUUAAUGAAUUUAAAACCCAUGGUUUAUCAUUGGCAAGAGGCAAGUUGACUUCAUCCUGUCAUUCCAGCCUGGGGUCUGCCAGCCAGCCCUCCUCCCCGACCCAGCGCCUAAGCUCACAGAGUGUCGUCGCCCACCUCCCUGGUCCUUGCUCUUGUUAACCCAAGAUGCUGCUACACAGAUGCCAAAUGGAAAUCUUCCACAGGGCUUUUUCAGUAAACACGUGAUGUGGAGUGCAAGCUCCUCCCCUUCCCACUAGAACAUACUUUAACAGAAAACGAGUCGGACCUUCUAGCUGCACUCUGUACUGUGUGCCGAGAAGGCAUUUCUAGACCCGUGUUUUUAAAGGAGGGAACUUUGGGGAUUGCCAGCCCCUGCUCCUCCUCCCAGGGAGCCAACUGUCCCUCCUCCCCUGUCCCUGGGCCCAUGGGGCCCGGCAGUGGCUGUGUCCCCUGCCUGAGGGCUCUGUGCCUCCUGCCUCAGAUGCGGCCUGUGCCAGAGAGGCUGCCUGUACAGCCAGGGUCAGUUUGGCCCCAAACAGGGAUUCAGAAACCAAAUGUGUGUUGUGGCCAUUUUAUGUGUGUCUCCGUCUUAUUUUAAUACCAAAUUCAUCAUGUAGUGAAAUUAUGUCAGGAGGUAUAUGAGUGACUGAAUUCUUAACUAUAGCUUAUCUGUGUUUUGUUAGCCCGAGGGAUAUGUGCAGGUUGUUGGCGCUAUUCAUGCACUGAAAUGAAAUCAUACUGACCAGUGUACACACAAGAUUAUCAGUGCCCGCCGCAUCCAUCACUAGGAAAGGAGAGAGCGUUUUCUGUUUAGGCUCACUGCGCAAAGGGAGGCCUUGGCUAAGUGGCAGUUUUCUUCUCCCUACUCCAGGUAGGAAGUCUGUUCAGCCACGGCUGGGCUGUGUGCGGGGCAGGGAGCGUGGCUGAGGAGCAGACAGCAGCGGGCCGGGCUGGCUGCCUGGUGAGCAGUUUGGUGCCUCGGGUGUUGUGCAUGCCCGGCUCAGUAUUUCCUCUGGGAUGCCAGUCCUGGAGUGUCUUCCUCAGAAGGUGCCGUGUCCCUUAGUGGGGGGAAGUACUGAUCUCACUUGGUGUAGAGGGUCACAGGGACCCCCCGAGGGUGCUGAGUGGCCUGCUACUGGCACGCAACCUGCCCCCGUGGGAUGAAGCCCCACCGCGUAGCUUGACCUUAGAGGGGACCCCACUCUAAGCAUCCUUUUUUUUAAACAGAGCCAUCUAGAUACAAAAGUCAGUUUCUUAAGAUGCCUCUCACUGAGCACAACACCAGUGUGAUGAGUGUAUAAAGAUGAGGGGUCCUUGCAACAAAGCAAAGCGUAGCCCAUGCUGGAAGAGGGCAUCUAUCCCCCUCUUCGGGUCUGCGCAGUGCUGGCCUUCCCUGAGCUGUGGGGAGCCAAGCCUGCCUAGCCCAGCUUCUCUGGCCUCAGGAACUCUGCCCUGUCAACCUAUCUGGGCUCACGUCUGCUUCUCCACACACAGUCUCUCGGGGAUGCCUUGCUACUGGGAGAGCCUCUGGAAUCAGAGCUAGUGUGUUGGUGCCCUUUUCAGAGCUCUGCUGUUCCUUUAUAAAUCCUAAAGAACUGAGUCUGGGGAGAGGAGAGGGGAUGCCAGCUGCUGCCUCUGACUUCAGGGAGAAGCAGACUUCUUAAUACUGUCUUACGUGCUCGGUGUGAUGGCUUCUUGCAAAUUAUUCUCUUAUAAAAGAGCUCGGCAGGAGUGGCAUCAGUGAGGCUCCCAAAGGAUGAAAUUUUAGCCGCCAAGUUCGUAUUCAUUUUCUGUUAUUCUUUACCUUCUGUUAGUCACACUAUUUUAUAACAUUAGGGAAUCUAAAAUAAUUCCUGUCAGGUCCCUGAAGGAAUGAAGGCUAACAUCUCCUUUGGGGAGAGCUUAGGACCCUUCAAACAACACUCAUGUCUGAGCGGCCAGAUUCCUCCUCCAGGCCCCAUUUUCCCUCAGGAAACCAACCUCUCAGAUGGUUGGAGGAGAAACACUGGGCUGUUGCUUCUUUGGGGCAGCAGGAGAAUGACUUUGGCUUGGAAGGCCUCUGCCAUUCAUCUCUACAAAGCCAGUGGGGUCCGGCAGAGAAAGACCGUGGAAUAGCUGCGGUCUCGAUGUGGCUGCUCUUUGGCACCUCCGCUGGACUGCCCUCCCGCGGCGGUGACCUUUUCAAGUGUGGAAGGGAGUGGGUCGAGUGGACCAGAUGCAGACCCCUGAGUUCUGGAUACUGAUGGGAGGCCUCACCCUCCUUUACGGGGCCUCUCUGGGUGGGACAGAGCCUCACCUGCUCCUGAGCAGCCACUGGUGCCCCACGGUUCCUCUGAAACUAAAUCCCUAGCAUCCAGAUAGUCCUGGGACACUCUGCCUGCUCUGUAAAUGAGGAGGGCUUUUCUCCUGCUGUUUGGAGGUUCCGUCCCUUCACUGCUUGUCCCAUAUGCGUCAGGCAAAUUCAAAAUCAUACAUUUAAACUCUUAGGAAAACAAAAUCUUAAGACUUACACAGAUAUCGGGGUGCUAAUCAACUGGCUUAAAUCUUGAUUCUUACAUAAUUUGAACUUGAAAGGUUACAUUGAACUCUGUUCUUUCCUCCCUCCUCACCUCACUCCCUGCAGGGAGUUCAAUGCCAUGUUGAAGUGGUUGGCAUCCCCAAGUGGGAGGGAGUGGGGCAUCUUACCAUCUUCUAAUGUGACUUCAAGGAACAGUGCAAAUGUUGAAUGCAGAGCUUCACACUAAUACGGAACAGUAACUGUGAGUAUAUUUACCUGUGCUGUCGUCAGCACUGUACACUAAAGGACCAGCUUUUCCAAGCCUAGGAAAAUAAUGGUAGAUACAAAUAGAAAUACAUUUUCCCUAGGAAAUAGAGCAAUAGGAAUUUGAGCUAAGCAGGUACCAUGAACUUCUGCCCUCAAAUUCUCUCUUUGGGUUGAGGAGCAGACCUGUAUAGGCCCUGGCUGAUCAAGUCUGUGUCCUGCCUAGUAAAAACACACAACCACCUCUGUCAUCUGAAGGCCAGCCGGGGAUCUGUAGCCAUCCUCGCCUUGCCUAGGCCCAGGAAGGUGAGGUCUCCUGGGCAACCAGAGUUGCCCCUGUGGUUCCCCAGGGGUGAUCCUAGGCAGAUGACUCACCCGGGCUGGCACAGGAAGGUGCUCACCUUGUUCUCUGGGGCUCCAAGCAAGAGCAGGCCAGGGAGGGCUGGCUUUGCACGCUAUGUAGCAUGACCCAAGCUCCCUGGUGGCAUGGGAAAAACUCCCCUCUGCUUUUGAGCCCAGAUAUGGGCUUUUCUUUGCAAAGGGUUGAGGAGAAAUACAAGACUGAGCUGGUAGGUUAGGGUCCAGAAGGCCUCUGAGGUGCCAUUGCUUACUUCCUUACUGAGGAAACUGGCUCUUGUCCUGGGCCAUGUAGUUCCAUUCUGGGCUCUAGGCUAGUGGUGCUUCUGUCCAUCAAGGGUAUCUGGGUGAGUUGUAGGUUAACCCAGAAUUUAGUAGGGAUAUAGGGGUUUGAAUAGGAAAGUGAUCUGGGGAUUCAGAAAUUUUUCUGAUGUAUCAAUGAGCAACUUCUCAGUGGAUUUUUAUACCUCAGGGUCAUUUGCAAAUCUUUAUCUUUUCCUAUUUCUUAGGUGUUCAAGUUGGUUAAUAGGAGAGAGACGUUCAGAGACUUCUAAGUUGAGGUUCAUUUGCCUCCGUUUGAGGGGUGAGUGGUGCACCAAUAGCUUGCUGCUGUUACUUAGCAAGGCUGUGACAAGUAGGCCUUCCUCCUCUAGCACUUGCAAGCUUUCUGUCUGCGAUCACGGUUUACUUGCCCAUUUCCCUUUUGCUACCUUCUUUCCUAUCUGGAGAUUCAUAUUCUAGAGUCCCUGGUCAACCCUACGGAUGCGAAGAAGAGAUGGCAGUUCACAGCAACUGCAUAGAGUAGGGAGCAGCUUUCCUCCCACCAUCCUAGGCUGGGGACCUUCUUUGCUUCUCACACCACUGUGGUUGGCUCAGCUCAAGUAAGCACGUUCUCUCUGUAUGCUAGAGCUACUGACAUCAUCUCUACUAGAAUUGUUUUAAAUAUCUUUUGAUGGGAAAUACCAGGUUGAACUUCAAGCAUCAUGGAAACAAAGGUUCUAGCUGCAAGAGAGUAAAGUUCUAGGUGUUUGUAUGCCAAGGUUUAUAUGUACACAGAUCCAACACAUACUGUAAGAAAGACUUGAGUACACAAGGUUUUCAGGUUUUAAUGCCCAUUGGGACCGUGAACAAAUGAGAAGAAUGGGAGCAUUGUCUUGCCUCGCUUGGAAGGACGCCUUCCGGCAUCUGAUCCACAUGGAUUCACUUUUAGGAUGCAGUUCUUUGGGGGCCAGAUUUGGCUGCAGAUUCACCCUGAAGAGAACUAUCCAAUGGGCCUGGUGGGGCUUGGGUGCCUGCCUUUUUUGUUGGAGGCUCAGACUUCUAGAGCAGAGCAAAGUUGGGAAGAAUGAGGUCUUAGGAUUCUCAUUCCCCAGAGAGCCCCAGCCUCGCUUCUGAUCAUUACUCCCCAAGUCUGAAUCUACUGUGAAGGUGAAGUUAUCAAUUUUUUCUUGUUUGAGUCCUUUAAACCCACAAAUGUAUAUGCUUUAUUUUAUAUUAUUUAUUAUGUACAUAUGCCUGUUAGUACUUCGUCUGUGACUAGGACAAGGUCUGUCUUGAAGCUUCCUCAUCCAUGGAUCCUAGGGUUCUGCUGUCCUUUAAGGCGGGUGAGAGGGUAGUGUUGUUUUUUAUAAACAGGUUGCUGCUUUUAUGUUGGCCCUAGCAUCCCCAGCCCCUUUAGUUGGGCCCACCUGUAUUCCUUAUGACCAGUGUUUUGGAUGAGGAUGGAGGCAGGUCUCCUACCUUGUGGGCAGGGCCUCUCAAGUACCUCCAUGAAAUAUUUCCAAGGUGGUUUCUUGGUGACAGGCUCUCUUCCCCUAUGUAGGGUACAGUACAGCUGUGAGUCCACGGCCUCCCUCCUCCCAAGGCAGGUCACUUGCCUGGCCCCACAGUGAUAAUGGUUUCUUCCACUUACCUUAGAUUGCAUAAUCCAUCUUUCUGGAUAAUGGAAGCUGCCUGCCUAUCUGGGCUCUUAAUAUGCCUUUUCUUGGUUUUGAGGCCCAGUGCCAACAUUGCCUUGGCCCUCAAGUAAGACCCUGCUUUGUGUCUGACUUUGAUCCUCCUCAGCCUUUAUUCACUGUAUCAUAGUGUACAGGUCAUGCAUUUGAGCAGUGAAGUUUUCUGAACACAGUAUUCAGAGCUGUGUACAUAAACCUAAAUAAGCACAAAUGACAUGUAUAGGAUUGAGCUGAUUGUCUUAAUGAAUGCAUUUUAUAAUUCAAAUGAUGUAGAUGUACAGUCUCUCCUAUUUAUUUUGUACCAAUUUAUUUGUAAAUUUUGUGAUUGUUUUACAAGGUUUUUGUUUAUUUCUAUUCUAUUUAGAUAAAUGAUGUUCUGUUCACCCUGCUAGCAGAUGUGUGUUCCCUCUUCCCUUUCAUCUGUGCAACACCAACCAUGCCAUUGUAUUCAGCUUGGCUGAACCAACUGCCCUACCCACUUGCCUGGCUUUGCUGGUGGGAAAGCUGGGACUGGAUCUCAGCAUGACAACAUAGAAGAGCAUCUUCUUUGGACAGUGUAAAGUCUUAAGAGAAGUGGGUACUAGUUCUGUGCCUCCAAGUCACAGCCUGGUACAGCCAAUCCUAGGGGGAAGGUGUCCUUCUUUGCAAGGAUUAUAAUCUGUUCUCCAUCAGUUACUCUCUACAUAAGAACAUUCGGAGUAUCCAGUCAAAUUGCCCCAGACAUUGGCUGCUCAGUCACUAAUAACAACACACAGUGCCGCUGGGCUAAGCCGGCAUUUCCUAGGUAAGACCAAAGGUCUCAUUCAGGCCUCUCAAUUGGCUCUUGAAAACAAGGAUGGCUUUAUAGGUCCUCCUCUGCUAUGCUAAGCCUGGGAGGAAGGUCGGAGCAGGCAUGGAUAGUCACUUUCAAGUGGAAAACAUCCGGCCUGAGUGUGGCGAGGCGUGUGCAGGUGGGUCUUCAGGAUUCAGUGGAUAUCCUGCAUUCCCCAGUAAUCGGUGUGUAUGAUACACGUUCUUUUCCAUCACUACUUUGUCUUCUGUUCCUUCUUACCCUCAUCACUCACAUGAGACCAGUCCCUGAAGAACUUACGGUGGAGCUUCAGGGACCCUCUGUGAUCCAUUCCUAAACCACAUCUUUUUGGAAUCCCUUUUCUCUCCACUUUUAGUCUCUAUUUUACAUUCCAAAGAGGAUCGUGCUCUGAAAAUUUAGCCUCUUGACUGGUCCAUUUAUAGUCUCCACUGAAUUUAUUUAACCGUGGCAUUUGCAGUCUUUUACUUACACUUGUUCUGUGGAUGGAGACAUUUCAGGGAAGAACUGCUGACAGAAUUGGCUUUCAGACACUGCCUGACCUAACUACCGCUCCCAUCUCCCCAGGUAUCGCCCAACUACCUGAAAGUAGAAUGAGGUGUAUCUUAGCCCAGUGAAAUGCUGUCUUCGAACCCUGCUUGCUUUCAUUAGAAGCAGGGCAGAAAGUGGCAGCAGAGCUAGGGAAAGAAAUCAUGGUAGCACAUUCACUCCCAGCCUCCUGCCUUGGUUUGUUUUUCCUGUUUUACUCACUUGGUCUAGAUGAGCCCUUAGCUCAAAUCAGGAAAUGCUCCAAGGAAAAUGGAGGCAAUUUUUCCUGCUGUCAAGAUGAGAUUUGCCUAAAACUCCCCCCUGCAUCCUCAGAGUGCGCACACAUCCGCUCAUUUCUAAGCUUUAUCGUGAUGCACCCGGGGUUUCUAUUUCACAAAAAUUGUGCUCCCUAGAGCCGUUUUUCAACUCGGCACUUCUGAGGAAACAAAUAUUGAUCAGAGGGUCUUGUAGAGAAAGUGGUUAAAAACUGACCUUUUUAUAGCCUGGAGUUGAUUUCUGGAAACUUAUUUUAUACUUUUUGAAGGUAAUUUAAAAGAGAUGAUUCUUUAUUAAAGCCAAAAAGUUGAAUUCUAUUAGGUGGAUAAUAAACUCUUUUGCUUUCUUUGUAUGGUGGUUUUGUCAUUUUCCCUCCAAGGGCCUCAUAUCUGUGCUCUUAUUUUCAAGCAGUCCCAGGACAAAGGGAUGGUUCUAGGGCCCUUUUCUCUGACUUUCUGCUGGCAUGCCAUCUCCCCUAGUGGAUUACUGAGGACUGAGGAUGCACGUUUCUAAGGGAGAAUUAGUUGCCCGACUUCUGAAGUGCUUUUCCUGUCAGGGUAUUAGUGACUGUGCAGUGUUCAAACAGGAGGCCAACACAUGAUAGGAAAUUUUAGAUGGGGCCAGUUUUCCUACUGCAGUUCUACUAAGUCAUUGACUUGAGGUCAGUGGGUCCAAAAAGUGACUUGUUUAAAGAUACCCACACACUCAAGUCAAAGAUAACUCUGGUGAGAACACUCUCUCAAAGACUGGACACUGAGUAAACAUUUUUCAGUGUGGGGAAGGUUUGCUUGGCAAAUCUUCUUUCCAAGUAUCUCAAGAACUUGUGAGACGUGGAAGGACUAUUGCUGCCUUUCGUGGGAAAAAUGUGUGCUCAGCUGCUUGGGCUCCAGUUUGUGUGGGAAGGUUUAUCUCAGGCCUUGUCUACUCCCCUCGCCAGACAUGGCUUUGGGAAGAGCUCCAUGGGAGACCAGAACAUCUGGGGACAUAGUUGUACCUAGUUAUUUUGUGUGAAGAAACAAAGGGACGAGAUUCAAAAUUCAUCAUUGUGUUUUAAAUUUAAAUUGGAAAACAUAGAUUCCUCAUCCUUAAACAGAGUCAGCAAGUUUGAGAUGAAAUGUUUGUGUUCAAUGGGGAGUACUUUUUUGUGUUAAAGCUCUACAGAGAAACUUCUGUAUAUAUUUUAUUUUUGAGAUCACAUACCUUUGUUGGAAUGAAUCAGACUGUUGUGGCCUUGGGAUGAAGACAUUGUGUGUGAGGACAGGGAAAAAUGGUUGAGAAAUCCAGGUUAAAGAAUAGAAAAGCUUUUUACUCAUUCUAUAAAUGAACAUGCUGCCUGUUUAAAGGACUUGCUUUCUGCUGUUUCUAGAUACCUAGCAGCGCGAGAACUGUGUGACGUGCUGCGUUCUUGUUACGGGAGGUGCGUGACGGGGCAGCGGGGGUUUCUGGAAGUCACCUGUUUCUGCUUUCUGGUUGCCUGUGCCUGUGGUCAUCCCUGCUCCUUAGCAGUAGUGCAUGUUUUUCUUCUAUCUGCAGGGUUGCUCUGGUAGCUCCAUGGUAGAGAUUUCACUCUCAGGGCCUCCCAAAAGUUGUGUAUCAUUUGAAAUUGUUCUAUUUGAGGAAAAACUUUUAAGAAAAGCUGGAUUCCCUGAUCACCACUAAAGAUCAUCAUGAGAAACAUAAGUAUUUGAGCCCUAAACUACUAAGCCCAGUGAGGAAUUGGAGCGUUAACUGUAUGGCAAUAGCUAGAUCAUAGUUACCAUUUUUCCCACCAUCAAAGACAGAUUAAAUAGUUUCCAUAACAUGGAAUGUGGGUAAGGUUCCUACCCUAAUACAGACUUAAAUAUGUAGUUGUCUCAGGCUAUUCGUGGUGAAUAAGCAGAGUAUUUAUUUUAAAAUGACCAGGCAGCCUUGGAAAAAUUGCUGGGCUUUAAAGUUGUUGACAAAGUAUUUCUUAAAUAAAUACAUCUGAUUUAGAAAUACCUAAACAUGGACAAAAUACUUCUAAAUCUGACAUGCAACUGCAUGUGGCUUUUUAAAGUGGUUUCUUAACAAUGCUAAUGUGACUUAAGGAUUUGUAGUUCUAUUAAAAACGACUUCUAAAAGUAUCUUAGGGUAGCUUGAAGGGUUUGCGUUAUUAUUUUAGGUCUCAGCAGAGGUAUGCUUAUGGCAAGAGAAAAAUCUUAGGUCUAAAUAGAACCCUAAACUUUCUUGGCUGUGACCAACUUUUCUGAAGUACACCAUCAGAGUUUUCACUGACUAUCUAUCUUUGCAGAGAUGAAUGAAUGUACUGGGCAAUUCCUCUGCCCAAGGAAACCCAGCAGGGCCUGGGUCUGCUGUACCACUGACCAACUGCUGGGGAGGCUAGGGGACCUGUCAGUACAUGCUGUAAGGUUGGGAGUUCAGUCUAGCAACCAAGAAGGGGUUGCCUGGUGUUCUACAAUGCCUAUAGUGUUUUCAAAAUGCCUGGGAAAAAAUUCUCAAAAGAAGUGGCAGAAUGGUCUUCUCACGGUAUAAAACUCCGCAGGAUUUUUUUUUUUUUUUUUUUUUUUUUUUUUUUUAAGGAAAAAAGUAUACCUUUUAAGUUCAGCUUCCUUAACUACUGGCAACAGAGAGAAAACUCAUAAUUUGUUUUAAAAAGCCCAGUUACAGCUGCCCUGCCUACCCAUGGACCAUUGACUUCCCAGCACACUCUUAAGAAUAAUAUACAGAGAGGCACCAUUUUGCUCUGGGUCUUAUGGAAUCCUAGAGCUCUUGAAUACGUUUUGGUGGUCCUACGGAGAGCUGUAACUAGCAGUGGAGUUGUUGCUUAUUCCAGCUGUGUGCUUUUCACUUUCCGAUCUUUGGACCCAGAGAAUCAUUUGCCAUGGAAUCAUCUGGCUAGUAAGACACUCUUAUAUGGAUGCAAUACAAAAAGUGGUAAAUUAAAGCAAAGCAAUCAUGUGGUCCUUACUCUAAAAGAGACAAUAUGUAAAUGUACUAUUAUAAUAAGGUAGCUCUGCAGAUGUAAUAAGCUACUCAUAAAUUAUUUGGGUUUAAGAAAACUUAAGACUAUGUUAAACUGGACAACAUCUCCAUCUUGAGUGAGAGUAAUUAGUAACUAGGAUGACCACACAUUCUCCUAACACGGGCAACAGUCUAGUCUAAUUGUUAUUGCAUUUCUGACCUGAUUCUUUUAAAGGGGCAUAUAUUCCCAAUAUAUACCAUUUAGAAUGUAUGUAUGUUUCUUGGAUGACUUAAUCUGAAGCCAUAUAAGUCCAAAGUAGUGAGACAGACAGUAUAUCCUUGACUAAGUUAUCAGGCUGUGUUCUCUGCUUAUAAAAUAAUUUUUUAAAAAGCCUCACUUCACAGUCCUGUUCCAAAAAUCUUUCUGUGAAAAAAUUGAGGCCUAUGUAACACCAUGAAUAUAAUCAUGUUAGAACAUAAUCAGUUCUUGAAUAUUUAUUUCCUUUAAGAGAAUAUCAAACUGAUGUCACCAAAUCUAAACCCACUUGAAGACCAAUAGCUAUUACAGUUGUACUACAGAAUAGGUCAAAGUCACCGUUAGAAAUAUUACACUUUAUUGAAUUCUGGAGCAGCUAAUCUACCCUCCCCUAUUGACCAAUGACAAGAAUGGAAGAAAAUAUACAAUGGUUAAAGAAAGAGUCUAUAACCACUGUUUGUUUAAAAUGUUGAAACAACUUUCACUGUACUGGUGAAACAGUUUUAAUACCCUAACAUACACAGUAAUGAUUCAUUCUUGUUUAAAACAAGAGGUGAUUUCGACUUGGGAUUGGGAUUUUUAUUUUUUGAGAUGGAGUUUUGUUCUUGUUGCCCAGGCUGGAGUGCAAUGGCACAAUCCUGGCUCACUGCAACCUCCGCCUCCUGGGUUCAAGCAAUUCUCCUGCCUCAGCCUCCUGAGUAGAUGAUGGGAUUACAGGCAUGCACCACCACGCCCAGGUAAUUUUGUAUUUUUAGUAGAGAUGGGGUUUCUCCAUGUUGGUAAGGCUGGUCUCGAACUCCCGACCUCAGGUGAUCCGCCUGUCUCGGCCUCCCAAAGUGCUGGGAUUACAGGCGUGAGCCGCCGUGCCUGGCCUUGACUUGAGAUUCUGAAGUGAAUUUAUUCACACUGAUUGUGCCCUCUACUUUAGUAAGGUUCUGGCUUACAGAGCCCUCUUCCCAUCCUCUGAUGUUCAAUUUUAAUAUACAGCAAUCAACUCUUAGAGGACAAAGAAAUCUGGAAUUGGGUAGCAUGAGCCACAGCUAUAUAGCCCACACUAAUGCAUGUUCUGUAGUAUAAGAAGGCAGUUCUUCCCUUUCUUUUCUGGGGGCUUGUUCCUUUGUCCACUUGCAGCUAAAUUCUUUCUAUAGAUUUAUCACAGAUAAGAAGGAGGUUGUUUUUGGAUAACAAAUAAGCAUUUGUGCUAUUAAACAAACAAAAGGUAAUAAGGAUACUGUCUUUUCCCUCAAAAUAGAAUCCUGCCCUAAAGCAACGCAAGUAGAGCAUACUUCUGUGCAAAGCCAGUGAUAGAGAAGCAGCCUUGCCAGAGUCACUGAGGAUGAAUUAAAGGCUUAUAAAAGAAAACUUGACCUUAACAGAGACUACAUUUGAUCAUGGAAAUAAUACAUUUCUCCACUGAUAUACAAUACCAUGUAAUGCACUGGAAAAGUUGGACCUUGGAGUAAUAGCACAAUUUGUAACAUUACAGAUCACCUCUUCCCACUCUUUGUUCCACUCUGAGACUCUUUCCUUUUCCUCGUGUAUCCAGAUACACUGACAUACGGAUGAUUUUAAAAGUGUCACAAGCCACAGUGGAGCCAUAUACAUGCAGUUCAGCCUGAUUUUACCCUUAUUUUCUUCUAAUACAGACUCCAUUACAAUUUUGGACCAUCUGCAGAGAGUACAGAUACACAAAACCAAAACAAGUAUCUAUGAUAAUAAAAUCUUCAGAAACUUUUCAGACGUACCUUUCAUGGAGCCCCCUCCCUCCCCCGAGUAGAACCCUAACAGGGACCUCGUUUGUUCCUGUGAGUCCUGCCAGGACUUGUUUAAUGGGUGCUUGGGGUUUUGGUUUUCCUCCUUAUUCUUCCUCCUCCUCCUCCUCUUCAUCAUCAUCUUCGUCAUGGCAGUGUGUAAUUUCCUGGGGGGCCAGUGGGAAGAGGUUGGGAGGUUUAAUCUCACUAAUUGACCGUGUCAGCUGGUGCCGCUUGUAGUCAGUGUCUUUGAAAUCCACUGAUGUGCGGUUCCGGGUGGCAAGAGGAGACUCCAUCUCAUUGAUAUCUACGUGUGUGUGCUCCACCGUUGAUUCAUGAGGCAUCUAGACAGAAAAAAGCUAGAGGCUCAGAAAGCAGGCAGAGCAAAGUAGCUACUCCCCAAAUCCUAACCCCUCUCCUCUGUUAGGUGGCCAUGCAAUUACAUCUAUAAUGGACCACAGGACAAGUCAAUAUAGACUUAUCUUCAUAGAACUACUUAUAGUUGCCUGUCUUCCUCUCUCCCUGCCCCUCAAAAUGGUGCCCAUAUUGUCUACUGCAGCUGGAAAUUGGAAAAGAUGGAGAGGGGAGUUUACUUUCUAUUUUACAGCAAAAACAAGAUAGUCCUGAAACAGAUCAGAAUAAAGGAAUGUAAAAACCA